GCUCAGUGCCUAGACGAUGGUGGUGGAAAGACGCUUCUGUGGGUUAGGUCCUAACGGUUAGGAAGGAUUCACAGGCGGGUCAUGAGGAAGGAGCAGACCCCUCGGGCAGAAGCCCGCGAGGAGCACUGGGUGUGGUGGGGGCAGGGGUGCCUCCUCUGUCAAGUGGAGAUCGGCGCCUCGCUCGUGCCUGCGAGUGCGCGCCGCGUCGAAUACAGCCGUACAGAACGCACUACAGGAAAGUGAAGCCGGGAGAGAGACUGGGAGGCGGCGCGGGGACUGGGGGCCGUAGACGCCUUUGCUCCCGGGCACUUGUUAGAAGAGCGAGUGGAUCGCGCUUCCUGUGCGUCACUGAAUCCUCAUGACGGCCACUGAAACGGACACGCAGGAUCUUUGCUUUUCAAGAGGGAACUGAGUCCAGGCCAGACUGGGUUGCUCCCCUUUCUCUCGGCCCCUCCACCUUUGCAAGUGCUGCUCCUUCUGCCUGGAGUGGCUCCUCCAGUCUUUUCCCGGCUCACUUCCCACCGUCCGGUGUCAGCAAAAACAGCACUUCCUCACAGCCCGUUGCAGCCCAGCAGUCGCCUUUUGCUUCUUUUGAAGCACAGCCCUGUGACCGCCUCGUGUCCUUUUGUUUUUCCUUGUCCCCCUUCCCCUCUGGAACAUAAGCUCCACAAAGGCAGGGACCUGGGAAUCCCGUUCGCCUGCAUUCCCCAGCAAACGCCUAACGAACCCAAUGGCCCAGGACUGAAAAUUCCUUUCCACUUCGGCUUUCCCCUCUACAUCCCAUCGGUUCUGUGGAGCUCGAGGGGCGUCACUGUGUGUGUGGCAGGGCACGGUGGGGGCUGAGAUCGUUUCCUGUUGGAACUUCUGGCCCAAGAAGCGCGGGUCACAAGGAGAGGGGUCAGUUCGGUUCAGAGCGACUCAGCCCCUCGACUCGGGUCUUAAAACCUCCGAGCCGCCAGUUCUGCCUCAGGCCGCGCCCCCUUAAAGCGCCACCAGACGCUGCGCCCCGUUAAAGCGCCACCAGACGCCGCGCCCCGUCCCGGCCUCCCCCGCGCGCUGGCGCGGGGCUUUCUGGGCCAGGGCGGGGCCGGCGAACUGCGGCCCGGAACGGCUGAGGAAGGGCCCGUCCCGCCUUCCCCGGCGCGCCAUGGAGCCCCGGGCGGUUGCAGAAGCCGUGGAGACGGGUGAGGAGGAUGUGAUUAUGGAAGCUCUGCGGUCAUACAACCAGGAGUGGCUGCUGCCUGAGUUAGAGGCCAAUAGGCCGCCCGCAUCAGCGGACGCGGAUCCUACCCCUCUGUGGAUUUGAAUUCACUAGUUCUCUCUGCAGCACUCCCAGAGCUUCACGUUUGAUGAUGCCCAACAGGAGGACCGGAAGAGACUGGCGGAGCUGCUGGUCUCCGUCCUGGAACAGGGCUUGCCACCCUCCCACCGUGUCAUCUGGCUGCAGAGUGUCCGAAUCCUGUCCCGGGACCGCAACUGCCUGGACCCGUUCACCAGCCGCCAGAGCCUGCAGGCACUAGCCUGCUAUGCUGACAUCUCUGUCUCUGAGGGGUCCGUCCCAGAGUCCGCAGACAUGGAUGUUGUACUGGAGUCCCUCAAGUGCCUGUGCAACCUCGUGCUCAGCAGCCCUGUGGCACAGAUGCUGGCAGCAGAGGCCCGCCUAGUGGUGAAGCUCACAGAGCGUGUGGGGCUGUACCGUGAGAGGAGCUUCCCCCACGAUGUCCAGUUCUUUGACUUGCGGCUCCUCUUCCUGCUAACGGCACUCCGCACCGAUGUGCGCCAGCAGCUGUUUCAGGAGCUGAAAGGAGUGCGCCUGCUAACUGACACACUGGAGCUGACGCUGGGGGUGACUCCUGAAGGGAACCCCCCACCCACGCUCCUUCCUUCCCAAGAGACUGAGCGGGCCAUGGAGAUCCUCAAAGUGCUCUUCAACAUCACCCUGGACUCCAUCAAGGGGGAGGUGGACGAGGAAGACGCUGCCCUUUACCGACACCUGGGGACCCUUCUCCGGCACUGUGUGAUGAUCGCUACUGCUGGAGACCGCACAGAGGAGUUCCACGGCCACGCAGUGAACCUCCUGGGGAACUUGCCCCUCAAGUGUCUGGAUGUUCUCCUCACCCUGGAGCCACAUGGAGACUCCACGGAGUUCAUGGGAGUGAAUAUGGAUGUGAUUCGUGCCCUCCUCAUCUUCCUAGAGAAGCGUUUGCACAAGACACACAGGCUGAAGGAGAGUGUAGCUCCCGUGCUGAGCGUGCUGACUGAAUGUGCCCGGAUGCACCGCCCAGCCAGGAAGUUCCUGAAGGCCCAGGUGCUGCCCCCUCUGCGGGAUGUGAGGACACGGCCUGAGGUUGGGGAGAUGCUGCGGAACAAGCUUGUCCGCCUCAUGACACACCUGGACACAGAUGUGAAGAGGGUGGCUGCCGAGUUCUUGUUUGUCCUGUGCUCUGAGAGUGUGCCCCGAUUCAUCAAGUACACAGGCUAUGGGAAUGCUGCUGGCCUUCUGGCUGCCAGGGGCCUCAUGGCAGGAGGCCGGCCCGAGGGCCAGUACUCAGAGGAUGAGGACACAGACACAGAUGAGUACAAGGAAGCCAAAGCCAGCAUAAACCCUGUGACCGGGAGGGUGGAGGAGAAGCCGCCUAACCCUAUGGAGGGCAUGACAGAGGAGCAGAAGGAGCACGAGGCCAUGAAGCUGGUGACCAUGUUUGACAAGCUCUCCAGGAACAGAGUCAUCCAGCCAAUGGGGAUGAGUCCCCGGGGUCAUCUUACGUCCCUGCAGGAUGCCAUGUGCGAGACUAUGGAGCAGCAGCUCUCCUCGGACCCUGACUCGGACCCUGACUGAGGAUGGCAGCUCUUCUGCUCCCCCAUCAGGACUGGUGCUGCUUCCAGAGACUUCCUUGGGGUUGCAACCUGGGGAAGCCACAUCCCACUGGAUCCACACCCGCCCCCACUUCUCCAUCUUAGAAACCCCUUCUCUUGACUCCCGUUCUGUUCAUGAUUUGCCUCUGGUCCAGUUUCUCAUCUCUGGACUGCAACGGUCUUCUUGUGCUAGAACUCAGGCUCAGCCUCGAAUUCCACAGACGAAGUACUUUCUUUUGUCUGCGCCAAGAGGAAUGUGUUCAGAAGCUGCUGCCUGAGGGCAGGGCCUACCUGGGCACACAGAAGAGCAUAUGGGAGGGCAGGGGUUUGGGUGUGGGUGCACACAAAGCAAGCACCAUCUGGGAUUGGCACACUGGCAGAGCCAGUGUGUUGGGGUAUGUGCUGCACUUCCCAGGGAGAAAACCUGUCAGAACUUUCCAUACGAGUAUAUCAGAACACACCCUUCCAAGGUAUGUAUGCUCUGUUGUUCCUGUCCUGUCUUCACUGAGCGCAGGGCUGGAGGCCUCUUAGACAUUCUCCUUGGUCCUCGUUCAGCUGCCCACUGUAGUAUCCACAGUGCCCGAGUUCUCGCUGGUUUUGGCAAUUAAACCUCCUUCCUACUGGUUUAGACUACACUUACAACAAGGAAAAUGCCCCUCGUGUGACCAUAGAUUGAGAUUUAUACCACAUACCACACAUAGCCACAGAAACAUCAUCUUGAAAUAAAGAAGAGUUUUGGACAAAAA